AACAGACAGGGACACGCCACUGGCCAGAGGGAGGAGGCUUCCACAGGUAGGAAGGCGCCCACAGGCUGGCUGCGGUCUGUCAUUACUCUGUGGGGGGUGCCUAUCUCUGCUCCUCUGUGGGUCAGGUCCUUUCCAUCCCUGUCUGGGGUCCUCCCCAUCUCCGUGUUCAACUGCGGUCUGUCUCUCCGUUUCCAAUUCAGGAACUGGUACCCCGUGGGUCCAUUCCUAUCCCCAGUCUCCGCCUCGGGCCUCCCCAUCUCCCCUGCUCCUCGACGCUAGCUACACCCUUCUCGGGAUGGGGUGCUCUGUACUGGGGGAUCCUCUCUAAAGUACAGUCCCCAGUCUUCCCUGGAUUCCCUGCUGGUCUCAGAACCCGCUCCAGGCUCCACCGCCUCCUUCCCUGCCUGACCUCCUCUCCUCCCAGGUCCAUCCGGAUGCCCUGCCCUCGGCCGUUCUGGCUCCGCCAUUCCCGGGCCCCCCAGGGCUCGGGUCCCAGCUCCCCAGGCUCGCUCUCUGCGCCCCGCUCCCCAAGCAGAGGGGAAGACCAGGAGGAGGAGGAGGAGGAGGAAGGGGACGGCAGCCCAGGCUCCGGCCCUAUCCUGCCCCCCGCCUCCCCGGUGGAGUGCCUCAUCUGCGUGUCGUCCUUCGACGGCGUGUUCAAGCUGCCCAAGCGCCUGGACUGCGGCCACGUCUUCUGUCUCGAGUGCCUGGCGCGCCUAUCGUUGGCCACGGCGGGCGGCGGCAACGCGGUGGCCUGUCCGGUGUGCCGCGCGCCCACGCGCCUGGCCCCCCGCCGCGGACUCCCCGCGUUGCCCACGCAGUCCGGUCUCCUGCCCCGCGACGCGCGCGCACCGCCCUCUCGCCAGGGCUCCGUGCGCUUCGACCGGCGCCGCGGCCUUCUCUACCUGCGGCCGCCGCCGCCCCCGCCCGGGCCGCGCAAGGCCCGCGCCCCGCCGCCCCCGCCGCCUCUGCGCCUGGGCCGCCCGCUGUCGCGCCGCUUGUCGCUGGCCAGCCCGGCCUGGGUCUUCAACGCUGCCGUGGCGCUGGCGGUGCUGGUGGCCGCGGGCCUCGUGGUCUCGGGCGUCUACAUCUUCUUCCUCAUCCCGCACGCCACCUCCUCCGGCCCCCCGCGGCCCCAGCUCGUGGCGCUCGCUCCAGCGCCUGGCUUCUCUUGGUUUCCGCCGAGGCCCCCGCCGGGGUCGCCCUGGGCCCCCGCCUGGACGCCGCGCCCCACGGGCCCUGACCUGGACACGGCCCUGCCAGGAACUGCAGAAGAUGCGCUGGAGCCCGAGGCGGGCCCCGAGGACCCGGCGGAGGCCGAGAGGACGCUGGACAGGCGAUCGGAUGGCACGUGGGGCACAGAGGCUGGCCCCGGCUGGGCCCCGUGGCCACGGGGCGCGAGGAGGCUGUGGGGCUCACAAUAA